AAUUCUGAGGCUCAGCCCUCCUCGGAGCCCACCAUCUCGAGGCUCCUGGACUGUAAGGGACCCCUGCAGUCCCCAGAGCAGAGGCCAGCAGGGGCUGAGACUAUGAGGCAAGCAGCCCAUCGACCCAGGCCUCCUUAGGACCAGCCCAGCCACCCAGCAAGCGAAAGAGCAGCAGCAGAGAGCAGAGCCGGAGAUAAAGGACCACAGCGGACCACUGGGGAUCACCCCCAGCAGCUCCUGAAGCCUCUGGCCGGGCUGAGGGGUUGCGACAGACGGCCAGACCCACAGACACUGACAGACACACAACGACACCGAUGCACACAGCUGCACGACACUGACACACUCAGAUACAACCAGGGACAGCAUCACAUACUGCCACAGCCCUGCAAUACAGACACCCACACACACACACACAAACAACUGGCAACUCUGAAAUGGGCAGACAGUGACACACAGCACCACCCCCCUCAACACACAGAAGUGGGGGCACCCAUCUUCCCAACACAUGAGACAGCAUUGACCUGCACGGACAGACCUGGAGACACACACACGCACCCUCACCCAGGCGCAGCUGUCGGUGGCCUCUGCACAUCCUCCCUACCCCCACAGGGACACCCUCGCUCCUCCACAUACUCGCGCACACACACAGCUACCAGCAAACAUAGCUCACAUACCCCUGGCUCCAGCUCCAGCAGCCCUGGCGCCUUCUGCAGCCUCCUUUGUGGGUGGGGAAGAGCUCAGCCAACCUUGGAUGGAGCGUCGGUGAAGCAAGAGCUCAGAGGGGAGAGGGGCUGGCCUGGCAUGACCCUCGCCAGUCCCCCCACCUGGCUGGGUGAUGUCCCCCGGCCCGGGUUCUGGGGCCCCUUGGCAGUACCAUGGAGCAACUGACAACCCUCCCACGGCCUGGGGACCCUGGAGCCAUGGAGCCAUGGGCACUGCCCACCUGGCAUAGCUGGACUCCAGGUCGAGGGGGUGAACCUAGCAGUGCAGCCCCAAGCAUCGCUGAUACUCCUCCGGCAGCUCUGCAGCUUCAAGAACUGAGGUCUGAGGAGAGUUCCAAGCCCAAAGGAGACGGGAGCUCCAGGCCCGUGGGGGGAACUGACCCUGAAGGAGCAGAGGCUUGUCUGCCCAGCCUGGGCCAGCAAGCAUCCAGCUCUGGACCCGCCUGCCAGAGGCCAGAGGAUGAGGAAGUGGAGGCUUUCCUGAAGGCCAAGCUGAAUAUGAGCUUUGGGGACAGGCCCAAUCUGGAGCUGCUGAGGGCCCUGGGGGAGCUGCGGCAGCGCUGUGCCAUCCUUAAGGAGGAAAACCAGAUGCUGAGGAAGAGCAGCUUCCCUGAGACAGAAGAGAAGGUGCGGAGGCUGAAGAGGAAGAACGCCGAGCUGGCGGUCAUUGCCAAGCGCCUGGAGGAGAGGGCCCGAAAGCUGCAGGAAACGAACCUGAGGGUGGUGAGUGCCCCCUUGCCCCGGCCGGGGACCAGCUUGGAGUUGUGUCGGAAGGCCCUAGCCCGCCAGCGAGCCCGGGACCUCAGUGAGACAGCCAGUGCACUGCUGGCCAAGGACAAGCAGAUUGCUGCCUUGCAGCGGGAGUGCAGGGAGCUGCAGGCCAGGCUCACUCUGGUGGGCAAGGAGGGUCCCCAGUGGCUCCACGUGCGGGACUUCGAUCGGCUGCUGCGCGAGUCCCAGCGGGAGGUGCUGCGGCUGCAGAGGCAGAUCGCGCUGCGCAACCAGCGGGAGACGCUCCCGCUCCCGCCGUCCUGGCCCCCGGGCCCUGCUCUCCAGGCCAGAGCAGGGGCGCCUGCUCCCGGGGCCCCGGGAGAGGCCACGCCCCAGGAGGAUGCGGACAACCUACCCGUGAUUCUAGGGGAGCCAGAGAAAGAGCAGAGGGUGCAGCAGCUGGAAUCGGAGCUCAGCAAGAAGCGGAAGAAAUGCGAGAGCCUGGAGCAGGAAGCCCGGAAAAAGCAGAGGCGAUGUGAGGAGCUGGAACUGCAGCUGAGACAAGCGCAGAAUGAGAAUGCCCGCCUGGUGGAGGAGAACUCCCGGCUCAGUGGGAGAGCCACAGAGAAGGAGCAGGUGGAGUGGGAGAAUGCGGAGCUGAGGGGCCAGCUCCUGGGGGUGACACAGGAGAGGGACUCAGCCCUUCGCAAGAGCCAGGGCCUGCAGAGCAAGCUGGAGAGCCUGGAGCAAGUGCUGAAGCACAUGCGGGAGGUGGCCCAGCGGCGGCAGCAGCUGGAGGUGGAGCAUGAACAGGCUCGGCUCAGCCUACGGGAGAAGCAGGAGGAGGUCCGGAGACUGCAGCAGGCCCAGGCUGAAGCCCAGAGGGAACAUGAAGGAGCCGUGCAGCUGCUGGAGUCUACCUUGGAUUCCAUGCAGGCCCGGGUUCGAGAGCUCGAAGAACAGUGCCGCAGCCAAACCGAGCAGUUCAGCCUCCUGGCACAGGAACUCCAGGCUUUCCGCCUGCACCCGGGCCCCUUGGAUCUGCUCACAUCUGCCCUGGACUGUGGGAGCCUUGGAGACUGCCCACCACCCCCCUGCUGCUGCUCCAUUCCCCAGCCUUGCCGGGGGUCUGGCCCCAAAGACCUUGACCUCCCGCCGGGCUCCCCUGGGCGCUGCACCCCAAAGUCUUCCGAGCCUGCCCCUGCCACUCUCACUGGGGUCCCUCGAAGGACAGCCAAGAAGGCAGAGUCUCUCUCCAACUCCUCCCACUCCGAGUCCAUCCACAACAGCCCCAAGUCAUGCCCUACACCUGAGGUGGACACAGCCAGUGAGGUAGAGGAGCUGGAGGCAGACAGUGUCUCCCUGCUCCCAGCUGCGCCAGAGGGCAGCCGGGGAGGAGCCAGGAUCCAGGUCUUCCUAGCACGUUAUAGCUACAACCCCUUUGAGGGUCCCAAUGAGAAUCCAGAAGCAGAGCUUCCGCUGACAGCUGGCGAGUACAUCUACAUCUAUGGCAACAUGGAUGAGGAUGGCUUUUUUGAAGGAGAGCUCAUGGAUGGCCGAAGGGGCCUGGUCCCUUCCAAUUUUGUAGAGCGUGUGUCGGAUGAUGACCUCCUGACCUCCCUCCCUCCAGAGCUGGCCGAUUUGUCCCACAGCUCAGGCCCUGAACUCAGUUUCCUGAGUGUAGGUGGGGGUGGCAGCAGUAGCGGGGGCCAAAGCAGUGUGGGAAGGAGCCAGCCCAGACCUGAGGAGGAGGAUGCAGGGGACGAGCUCAGUCUGAGCCCAUCACCGGAGGGCCUGGGCGAGCCUCCUGCCGUGCCUUACCCCCGCCGUCUGGUGGUCCUCAAGCAGCUGGCCCACAGCGUGGUGCUGGCCUGGGAGCCGCCUCCUGAGCAAGUGGAGCUACACGGCUUCCAUAUCUGUGUGAAUGGGGAGCUGCGACAGGCCCUGGGGCCUGGGGCGCCACCCAAGGCCGUGCUGGAGAACCUGGACCUGUGGGCCGGGCCCCUUCACAUUUCUGUCCAGGCCCUGACUAGCCGGGGCAGCUCUGACCCACUGCGCUGUUGCUUGGCGGUGGGUGCCCGGGCCGGAGUGGUGCCCAGCCAGCUGCGGGUCCAUCGGUUGACAGCCACAUCUGCUGAGAUCACCUGGGUGCCCGGCAAUAGCAACUUGGCCCAUGCCAUCUACCUCAAUGGGGAAGAGUGCCCACCUGCCAGCCCCAGUACCUACUGGGCCACCUUCUGCCACUUACGGCCUGGCACACCCUAUCAGGCCCAAGUGGAGGCUCAGCUCCCACCCCAAGGGCCCUGGGAACCAGGCUGGGAGAGGCUGGAGCAGCGGGCUGCCACCCUGCAGUUCACCACACUCCCAGCAGGCCCACCUGAUGCCCCUCUGGAUGUGCAGAUCGAGCCUGGGCCCUCCCCUGGGAUCUUGAUCAUCAGUUGGCUCCCAGUCACCAUCGAUGCUGCUGGCACAUCCAACGGUGUCCGGGUCACAGGCUAUGCCAUCUACGCUGAUGGGCAGAAGAUCAUGGAGGUGGCCUCACCCACGGCAGGCAGUGUACUGGUGGAGUUGUCCCAGCUGCAGCUGCUGCAGGUGUGUCGUGAGGUGGUCGUGCGCACCAUGUCGCCCCACGGGGAGUCGGCGGACUCCAUCCCGGCUCCUAUCACUCCCGCCCUGGCUCCGGCCAGCCUGCCAGCCCGAGUCUCCUGCCCCUCACCGCACCCAAGCCCAGAGGCCAGAGCGCCCCUUGCUUCAGCCUCCCCAGGGCCUGGAGACCCCAGCUCUCCUCUCCAGCACCCUGCUCCCCUUGGAACUCAAGAGCCUCCAGGAGCACCCCCUGCAAGCCCUUCCAGAGAGAUGGCAAAAGGGUCCCACGAGGACCCUCCAGCACCUUGCUCCCAGGAGGAGGCUGGGGCAGCAGUGCUGGGCACCUCAGAGGAGAGGACAGCCAGCACAUCUACCCUGGGUGAGAAGGACCCUGGCCCCGCAGCUCCCUCACUGGCCAAGCAGGAGGCCGAGUGGACUGCAGGAGAGGCCUGUCCGGCCUCCAGCUCCACCCAGGGAGCACGGGCCCAGCAGGCGCCAAAUACCGAGAUGUGCCAAGGAGGAGACCCAGGGUCUGGGCUGAGGCCCAGGGCUGAGAAGGAGGACACAGCAGAGCUUGGGGUUCAUCUGGUGAACUCCCUCGUGGACCACGGCCGCAACUCAGACCUGUCAGACAUCCAGGAGGAAGAGGAAGAGGAGGAGGAGGAGGAGGAAGAGGAGCUGGGUUCCAGGACUUGCUCCUUCCAGAAGCAGGUUGCUGGCAACAGCAUCAGGGAGAAUGGGGCCAAGUCCCAGCCCGACCCCUUUUGUGAGACUGACAGCGAUGAGGAGAUCUUGGAGCAGAUCCUGGAGCUGCCCCUCCAGCAGUUCUGUAGCAAGAAGCUCUUUAGCAUCCCGGAGGAGGAGGAAGAGGAAGAGGAGGACGAGGAGGAGGAGAAGUCAGGGGCAGGCUGUUCUUCCCGAGACCCUGGCCCGCCUGAACCUGCAUUGCUGGGGCUGGGCUGUGACAGUGGUCAGCCCCGAAGACCUGGCCAGUGUCCCUUGUCUCCUGAGUCCUCCAGGGCUGGAGACUGCCUGGAAGACAUGCCUGGAUUAGUUGGUGGAAGCAGCCGGAGGAGAGGAGGGGGCUCCCCUGAGAAGCCCCCAAGCCGCAGGCGGCCUCCAGAUCCCCGAGAACACUGCAGCCGACUUCUCAGCAACAAUGGGCCCCAGGCCUCUGGACGACUGGGCCCCACACGGGAGAGGGGUGGCCUCCCCGUAAUUGAGGGCCCCAGGACUGGACUAGAGGCUAGCGGGAGAGGCCGGCUGGGCCCUUCCCGGAGGUGCUCCCGUGGCCGGGCGCUGGAGCCUGGCCUGGCCAGCUGCCUUUCCCCCAAGUGCUUGGAAAUCAGCAUUGAAUAUGAUUCGGAGGAUGAGCAGGAGGCGGGCAGCGGGGGCAUCAGCAUCACCAGCUCCUGCUACCCUGGAGAUGGGGAGGCCUGGGGCACAGCAACUGUAGGAAGGCCCAGGGGGCCUCCGAAGGCCAAUUCAGGCCCCAAGCCCUACCCACGCCUCCCAGCCUGGGAGAAAGGGGAACCAGAGCGGAGAGGCCGCAGUGCGACGGGCAGAGCCAAGGAGCCACUCUCCCGGGCAACAGAGACCGGAGAGGCCAGAGGGCAGGACGGCUCUGGGCGGAGGGGCCCCCAGAAGAGAGGUGUCCGAGUCCUCAGGCCAAGCACUGCAGAGCUAGUCCCUGCGAGGAGCCCCUCAGAAACACUGGCUUACCAGCACCUACCCGUCAGGAUCUUUGUGGCUCUGUUUGACUAUGACCCCGUGUCAAUGUCGCCCAAUCCUGAUGCUGGAGAAGAAGAGCUUCCCUUCCGAGAGGGUCAGAUCCUGAAGGUGUUUGGGGACAAGGAUGCCGAUGGCUUCUACCAGGGCGAAGGUGGGGGCCGGACAGGCUACAUUCCCUGCAACAUGGUGGCUGAGGUGGCUGUGGACAGCCCUGCUGGGAGACAGCAACUGCUCCAGCGGGGUUAUUUGUCCCCAGAUAUUCUCCUUGAGGGCUCAGGGAAUGGUCCGUUUGUGUACUCCACAGCCCACACAACUGGGCCUCCUCCCAAGCCCCGCCGCUCCAAGAAAGCUGAGUCGGAAGGCCCUGCCCAGCCCUGUCCAGGCCCCCCUAAGCUGGUCCCCUCUGCUGACCUGAAAGCUCCCCACUCCAUGGUGGCUGCAUUUGACUACAACCCCCAGGAGAGUUCCCCCAAUAUGGACGUGGAGGCAGAGCUGCCCUUCCGGGCAGGGGAUGUCAUUACUGUGUUUGGGGGCAUGGACGAUGACGGUUUCUACUAUGGGGAAUUAAAUGGACAAAGGGGCCUGGUUCCAUCCAACUUCCUGGAGGGCCCUGGGCCUGAGGCAGGCGGCCUGGACAGGGAACCCAGGACACCCCAGGCUGAGAGUCAGAGAACGAGGAGGAGAAGAGUCCAGUGCUAGAUGGAGAUAGAUAUAUGUAGAGAGAGCAACAUGACUGGGGCUGCACCACACAAGGGUCCCCAGGGCCCCCAGGUGGGCCUUGUACCCCCAGCUCUGGCAGCGCCCCCAGGAUUGAACGUGGGGAGCCCCAGGGCAGAAGCGAGAAGGUGUGGGGUUUCUUCUCCAAGGGGAAGCAGCUCCUCAGGAGGCUGGGCUCUGGGAAGAAGGAGUGAAGCUGUGGCCCAUCCUGCAGGCAGAAGAGGCCCUGAGAGGCCCCCAGAUCACUGUCUCUGCUGAGCAGGGAAGGCUCAGACUGGGCCCAGAGCCCCCGUUCUUCUGCGUUAACACUGUGGCAUUCAGAGGGAAUCAAAGAGCCUUGGUGAAGGUCAGAGCUAAAUGGCUCCUUAAGGAUGAACUCUCUAGAGAAGCACCUUCCUCCUACAGGAGGGGAAACUGAGCCCACAGUGAGUAUGUAACUUGACCAAGGUCACUGAGCCAGGACUGGACCCAGGACCCUCGCGUCCUGGUCCACCCACCUCGUCUACUAGUGUCCCACAGUGCUGCGCUAGUCCCUUCUGCCACCCUUCCCAGUCCCAGGACGGGCCCUGGAGGGAGAAAGGAGCCUGUGCCCCCUGAUGGCUCUGGCUGUCCUGAUCCUGUCUUCCCUCCCCUGAAGGAAAGUUUGCACUGGAUUUUAUUGGAGCCCCAUCUCCCCAGCGGGCAGGCGGGCGGAGCCUGUAUAUAUGUAUAUACUCAGUGCCUCAGUUCAGCUUCCUCCACCUCGCUUCCACUGCACAGGCCCAGGAAGGAGAAAGGCCAAGCCAAAGUGGGCCCCACCCUGCCCCCGUCGUGCUCCAUCCUUCCCUGCCGGGGCCUGCUGGCCCCUGUAAGGUCCCGCCCCCAAAGACCCUGGGGCCAGCGGGGCCGAAAGCGGAGUUGGGUUUGCCUUAUUUUGCUCAUUGGAUUCAAGUUCUUUUGCAUAGUUUUCUUCUAACCCCUGUUGGAGUCCAGGGGCUGGAGAAAAGGACAGAUUUAUGCAGCUAUUUUCAUACAUUCCCUGUUCAGAGUGGGGUAGGGGUUCUCCGCCGUUACCCGAUCCACUCCAUCCCCCACCCUCUGAGGGGUGAGUGUGUCUUUGCAUGUUUCCUUUGCUGUGGUGGGAGAUAGUUUGACUGAACCCCCACCUUGACCUUGGUCUCCAGGGGUGUGGAAUGGUGGGGGAAUUUGUUUAAAAAGACAUUUUAUUAUAAUAAAGUCUAUUUUCACAAAA